GUCAUUGACAGUUUUUGAAGCACAUUUCACACAUAUUUUAUUGUCUCCUUGUAACUGUGAGACCAAUGAGGUGGAUAUUAUUGAUCAUAGUCCUAGGGCAACUAAGGGAUGGAAGUAUGUGUGUUGUGCUAAAUUCCUGAAAUUCAUUACUUGGGAAGCUGAGUUUUGAAUCCAGUUUCUGAGUCUUCAUUUUGGAUCUCAAUCCUGUGUUUUUCCCACCAACCCAGUGAAUAUUAUUACAGCAUCUUGUGUAAGAAGGAUAAAGCAGGGUUAAGCAGGAUAUGUUUUUAAAAAAAUUGUGACACUCAUCCUACUCAGAAGUACAACUGAAUUCACCAUAAGUAAGGGCUUUCUAAAGGAAGCUUUCAAGUUAUCCUGGACUCUGGUGAAUCUUGAGAGCCUACAUUUAUGUAGAUUAGAUGUUAAAAGUUUGCAAAGCUCUCACGUUGUAAAUGUCAUAAGCAUUUGCUGUGAAAUAAUAGUAGAGAAGCAGAAAGAAACCAAGAUGGAUAGAUUCCCACUCAGUCUCCCUAUAAACUUGCAACAUGUUGCAUAAUAAAUAUGGAUGUAGCAGAGACAUCGUGGUAUCUUUAUGCUGUGCUCAGUAUCCACAGAGGGAUAAAUGCUGGGUUCAUAAAAAGUGGGUUUCAAAAAUGUAUUUGUUUGUUUUUCCAGUGGAUUCAUUGGUAGGAAGAACUUCUAAACCCACUCUGAAGAUCCAUAAGCACUAGAUCUUGUAGGAAGGAGUUAAUGUAUUCAGAAGAGUCAGUUCUUUCCCAAUAUAUUGAGGGUUUGCUUGAGGAUUUAUCUUGUGAAAUAGAUUUCAAAAGUGGAAAAGUAGUGCCUUAACUGACUGAGAUCUAGAACAAAUGGAUUUCAUGUGAUUUUGAUAAAAGUUUUAUAUCAGAGUGGCCUUUAAGAAAUUCUAACAGGAAAAGGGGUUGUCUCCCUCUUUGAUUUUCCCAAAUUUGGCAGGAAGAGGUCAACAGAGGGCUGGUGAGGCAUUUGAAACUCAGCAUUUGUGUUUACAGACAUUCAUAUAAAAAGUGGCCAGGAAAAGAGAUAUAGAAACCAAUGCAUGUUAAAUGAGACCUGUUCUGGGGGAUAUCUGAGAUGCAGGUCCUUUCCUGCUGCUAACCAGCUGUAUGGCUUUGAGGAGUCUCCAUUUUAUGAGUUCCUCUACUGUAUUAACAUAGAGACUAAUAAUGUCCACUAUGUGUAAUUGACAGUGCUGUUUAGAGAUAAUCAAAUGAAAGCAUGCAUGUGAACUUGCCCCACAAGCUUCUAAAGUAGUUCACGAAUGUAAGGCAAAUGGAUAAUUUUAGAGCUUUUGACUUGGAAGUAUACUUCCCUUAAUUUAAAAAUCCAUCUUGGUCCUUGUUUCCUAUCUUAGUGGGACCAGUUAGGAAGGAAAAAAAUUAGAGUUUAGCUGUAAAAUGGUGUAUGGUGCCAUGUUUGAUCACACAUGCUCUGGAAACCAAAGGACUUCAGUUAAGUUCUUGCCUCUGUCAUUUAGCUGUAGUUACCAUAAAUGGGUUAUAUAACCUCUUUAAGCCUCAAUUUGUUCAUCCGUACAAGGGUUGCAAUUACUACCUUUUAGGGGCUUUGUGAGAAUUGUGGUGAGGUGAUACAUGUGUAACCAGUAUAAAAUGAAACUUUCCUUCUUGCCUCUACUGUUCCUUUAAUUUCUAUCCUCUUGAUCAUUCUCUUCUAGUCCCUGAAUGCAAACAUUAGUAAGCCCCACAAUGUUGUACUUACUCCUAGAUAAUAGAUUGUCCUAAUAUUAUUUUAAGUCACAAACUCAGUUAAUUUAAACCAAAAUAAAAAUUAAUCAUGAUCAUUUAAAUGUAUAGUUUAAGAGAUUAACAAAAACCCUGAAUUUCAUUUAAUAUUUAACUGUUCUCCCCUUCCCUUUGUUUCAGGCUCAAAGGGAAAGAGGAUUUAGUAAGUGGCUUGAUUUCUCUUCUCUGCCUUCCAUUCCACUCCACCCCCAGGUGCCCAAGCAAGGAAAGAAAUAAUGAAGAGACACAUGUGUUAGCUGCAGCCUUUUGAAACACGCAAGAAGGAAAUCAAUAGUGUGGACAGGGCUGGAACCUUUACCACGCUUGUUGGAGUAGAUGAGGAAUGGGCUCGUGAUUAUGCUGACAUUCCAGCAUGAAUCUGGUAGACCUGUGGUUAACCCGUUCCCUCUCCAUGUGUCUCCUCCUACAAAGUUUUGUUCUUAUGAUACUGUGCUUUCAUUCUGCCAGUAUGUGUCCCAAGGGCUGUCUUUGUUCUUCCUCUGGGGGUUUAAAUGUCACCUGUAGCAAUGCAAAUCUCAAGGAAAUACCUAGAGAUCUUCCUCCUGAAACAGUCUUACUGUAUCUGGACUCCAAUCAGAUCACAUCUAUUCCCAAUGAAAUUUUUAAGGACCUCCAUCAACUGAGAGUUCUCAACCUGUCCAAAAAUGGCAUUGAGUUUAUCGAUGAGCAUGCCUUCAAAGGAGUAGCUGAAACCUUGCAGACUCUGGACUUGUCCGACAAUCGGAUUCAAAGUGUGCACAAAAAUGCCUUCAAUAACCUGAAGGCCAGGGCCAGAAUUGCCAACAACCCCUGGCACUGCGACUGUACUCUACAGCAAGUUCUGAGGAGCAUGGCGUCCAAUCAUGAGACAGCCCACAACGUGAUCUGUAAAACGUCCGUGUUGGAUGAACAUGCUGGCAGACCAUUCCUCAAUGCUGCCAACGACGCUGACCUUUGUAACCUCCCUAAAAAAACUACCGAUUAUGCCAUGCUGGUCACCAUGUUUGGCUGGUUCACUAUGGUGAUCUCAUAUGUGGUAUAUUAUGUGAGGCAAAAUCAGGAGGAUGCCCGGAGACACCUCGAAUACUUGAAAUCCCUGCCAAGCAGGCAGAAGAAAGCAGAUGAACCUGAUGAUAUUAGCACUGUGGUAUAGUGUCCAAACUGACUGUCAUUGAGAAAGAAAGAAAGUAGUUUGCGAUUGCAGUAGAAAUAAGUGGUUUACUUCUCCCAUCCAUUGUAAACAUUUGAAACUUUGUAUUUCAGUUUCUUUUGAAUUAUGCCACUGCUGAACUUUUAACAAACACUACAACAUAAAUAAUUUGAGUUUAGGUGAUCCACCCCUUAAUUGUACCCCCGAUGGUAUAUUUCUGAGUAAGCUACUAUCUGAACAUUAGUUAGAUCCAUCUCACUAUUUAAUAAUGAAAUUUAUUUUUUUAAUUUAAAAGCAAAUAAAAGCUUAACUUUGAACCAUGGAAAA